AACUGUGCUAUGGAGUAGAAGCAGGAGGUUUUCAACCUAGUCACAGAGCAGCACCUACCCCCUCCUCCUUUCCACACCUGCAAACUCUUUUACUUGGGCUGAAUAUUUAGUGUAAUUACAUCUCAGCUUUGAGGGCUCCUGUGGCAAAUUCCCGGAUUAAAAGGUUCCCUGGUUGUGAAAAUACAUGAGAUAAAUCAUGAAGGCCACUAUCAUCCUCCUUCUGCUUGCACAAGUUUCCUGGGCUGGACCGUUUCAACAGAGAGGCUUAUUUGACUUUAUGCUAGAAGAUGAGGCUUCUGGGAUAGGCCCAGAAGUUCCUGAUGACCGCGACUUCGAGCCCUCCCUAGGCCCAGUGUGCCCCUUCCGCUGUCAAUGCCAUCUUCGAGUGGUCCAGUGUUCUGAUUUGGGUCUGGACAAAGUGCCAAAGGAUCUUCCCCCUGACACAACUCUGCUAGACCUGCAAAACAACAAAAUAACCGAAAUCAAAGAUGGAGACUUUAAGAACCUGAAGAACCUUCACGCAUUGAUUCUUGUCAACAAUAAAAUUAGCAAAGUUAGUCCUGGAGCAUUUACACCUUUGGUGAAGUUGGAACGACUUUAUCUGUCCAAGAAUCAGCUGAAGGAAUUGCCAGAAAAAAUGCCCAAAACUCUUCAGGAGCUGCGUGCCCAUGAGAAUGAGAUCACCAAAGUGCGAAAAGUUACUUUCAAUGGACUGAACCAGAUGAUUGUCAUAGAACUGGGCACCAAUCCGCUGAAGAGCUCAGGAAUUGAAAAUGGGGCUUUCCAGGGAAUGAAGAAGCUCUCCUACAUCCGCAUUGCUGAUACCAAUAUCACCAGCAUUCCUCAAGGUCUUCCUCCUUCCCUUACGGAAUUACAUCUUGAUGGCAACAAAAUCAGCAGAGUUGAUGCAGCUAGCCUGAAAGGACUGAAUAAUUUGGCUAAGUUGGGAUUGAGUUUCAACAGCAUCUCUGCUGUUGACAAUGGCUCUCUGGCCAACACGCCUCAUCUGAGGGAGCUUCACUUGGACAACAACAAGCUUACCAGAGUACCUGGUGGGCUGGCAGAGCAUAAGUACAUCCAGGUUGUCUACCUUCAUAACAACAAUAUCUCUGUAGUUGGAUCAAGUGACUUCUGCCCACCUGGACACAACACCAAAAAGGCUUCUUAUUCGGGUGUGAGUCUUUUCAGCAACCCGGUCCAGUACUGGGAGAUACAGCCAUCCACCUUCAGAUGUGUCUACGUGCGCUCUGCCAUUCAACUCGGAAACUAUAAGUAAUUCUCAAGAAAGCCCUCAUUUUUAUAACCUGGCAAAAUCUUGUUAAUGUCAUUGCUAAAAAAUAAAUAAAAGCUAGAUACUGGAAACCUAACUGCAAUGUGGAUGUUUUACCCACAUGACUUAUUAUGCAUAAAGCCAAAUUUCCAGUUUAAGUAAUUGCCUACAAUAAAAAGAAAUUUUGCCUGCCAUUUUCAGAAUCAUCUUUUGAAGCUUUCUGUUGAUGUUAACUGAGCUACUAGAGAUAUUCUUAUUUCACUAAAUGUAAAAUUUGGAGUAAAUAUAUAUGUCAAUAUUUAGUAAAGCUUUUCUUUUUUAAUUUCCAGGAAAAAAUAAAAAGAGUAUGAGUCUUCUGUAAUUCAUUGAGCAGUUAGCUCAUUUGAGAUAAAGUCAAAUGCCAAACACUAGCUCUGUAUUAAUCCCCAUCAUUACUGGUAAAGCCUCAUUUGAAUGUGUGAAUUCAAUACAGGCUAUGUAAAAUUUUUACUAAUGUCAUUAUUUUGAAAAAAUAAAUUUAAAAAUACAUUCAAAAUUACUAUUGUAUACAAGCUUAAUUGUUAAUAUUCCCUAAACACAAUUUUAUGAAGGGAGAAGACAUUGGUUUGUUGACAAUAACAGUACAUCUUUUCAAGUUCUCAGCUAUUUCUUCUACCUCUCCCUAUCUUACAUUUGAGUAUGGUAACUUAUGUCAUCUAUGUUGAAUGUAAGCUUAUAAAGCACAAAGCAUACAUUUCCUGACUGGUCUAGAGAACUGAUGUUUCAAUUUACCCCUCUGCUAAAUAAAUAUUAAAACUAUCAUGUGACUUCAUGUAAUCAGGCUGAACAUUUCUACAAUUACUAGAUGUAUUAGACGUAAGUAUUUUCUUUAGUUAAACCACCCAUGUUAGAAAUGUUUUCUGUAGAAUUUAUAAACAACUAUCAAUGCAGACAAUUUAAUAAGCCUGGGGAUGAUUUACUUACAGUAAACAUUUAUCAAAUUGUACAUUUGUGCUAUCAACAAUUAAUAAGCAAAUAUGUGAAAAUAGUUUCUGUCUUCUAUGAAGUUAGAUAUUUGAUGGUUAAAACCCCUAUAAAUCAUAGUUUCAUAUGGGAAAAAAUAAUUGAAAUACAGUGUAAAUUUAAAUAAUUUAUUAAGUAUAGCAAAUAAUUGAAAUAUGGUGGACUAAAUUUUGUCAUAGAAAUAUGUGCAAGUUAUAGUAGUGGCUCACAUGAGAGGUAAUCAAUUCUGCUAAUAGUAGCAGAAUGAGUGCAGUGGAACAUGAAAAACUUGAGGAGAUAACAGUUGAGGUGGGUUUCCAUAGAUGCAUAAUAGUUCAAGAGCAAGAUUUGGUGGGGAGGCACUAUUCAAGACAGGGACUAAGUUCAAAAUCCAAGACGUAUGCUGGGACACACCUCUGACAGGUUGGCAUAAAGGAGGCUUAAUCAAACUAUUUUUCUUCUUCUGAAACAGAAGCAAUAAUUUUCAUUUACAUUUGACAUAUCCCGAGGUAAUAUUAACAUUAGGGAAAGUUACUCUUUUCCAUCUUUCCACAUUCUUGCAGGACCAUAAAAUCUGAAUUUUCCAGUAUUUUUAAUAAGAGGGAAGAAACCUCUCUUUUUCUUCUCUUUUUCAUCUCCCAAGAGAUCCUCCUCUCAUGACUACAGUUGAAUAGGUGGUUUCUAUUGGAAGACAUUCAGGAAUUCAAGGUGCAUGUCCAUAAAUGGACUUUUUUUGUUGUUGUUCAGAGCUGGACCUUGAAUGAUGCAUCCUUCUCUCUGUUGUAACCAUGAAUAAUGCACCCUUCAUGCUAUAGCCUUUAACGAUUCACCCUUCUUAUUGUAACCUUGAAUGAUUCACCCUUUAUGGUGUAGCCUUGAGUGACGCACCCUUCAUGUUGUAGCCUUCAAUGAUGCACACUCCAUGUUAUAGCCUUGAAUGAUAUACCCUUUAUGCUGCAGCCUUUCUCUUAUGGGGAAAAGCCUGCAGAUAUCCUGCUGCUUAACUGACAAGUGUGGUGAGAAAUAAGUAGAAAUCUAAAGAGGGGAAGACCAUUUUGGACACUUAUCUGCAAGGCAGAUCCAACACACUUUUCCAGUAGUCAAGCUACUUCUAAUUUUGUUCAGUAUCAAAAUGAGAAACAGGCCUGAUUCUCCAGCACUCUUGUCAACACAACUUCCCCCCAUAUUUAUAUAUAUACACACACAUAUAUAUCUUUAUAUAUAUACACACAUAUAUAUCUUUAUAUAUAUAUAUUUAUAUAUAUAUCUUUUUGCAUAUAUACAUAUAUAUGUAUCUUUAUUUCCUUUGAAAUAAAGAUAAAUAUAGCUGAUUUCUUUGGCUUCGACACUUACUAUUUGCAUGACUAAGGGAAGCUAGUUAACCUUUCUGUGACUCAUUUCCUUGUCCAUAAAAUGGGAAUAUUAAUUGUACAUGUCUUAUGGAUUGGUGUGUGAAUUCAGUUAGCGAGUGUAGAAUAUAACUUAUAGAUCAAAGUAGAGUAAAUGGAAAGGGCUCAACUAUGGUGUUGCUACUGCCAUUGUUAUUACAGGCACACAGUUCGAGCUAUAAUCAUUUCAAGGGAAAUUCUUAUGUGUCAGUUCUGGAUCGAGGUCUGAGAUUCUGCAUUUCAAACAAACUUCCAGGAAUGCUGCUGCUUCUUGGUCCACACUUGGAGAAAUAAGUCAGCAGAGAGUCCUCUCGUUUCCUAUUGUACCAUGUCUGUCUUUUGUCUCCUGCUUAUUGGCCUCUGUAAGGAACUCACAGCUGCUAUAAUAAAGUACCAAAAACUGGGUGGCUUAAAACAACAGAAACUUACUUUCUCACAAUUCUGGAGGCUAAAAAUUCAAAAUCAAGGUGUCAGCAGGGUCAGAUUCCUUCCAAAGCCUUUAGGAGAGGACCUUUCCUUGCUCCUCCUAGGUUUCUGGUUAAAUCUAGGUGUUCUUUGCCUUAUGGCAGCGUGACUCUAAUUUAUGCCUCCAUCUUCACCCUCACAUGGCCUUCUCUCUCAUGUGUUUGUGUCUUUUCUCUUCUUCUUCUAUGAACAUGAGUUAUAUUGGAUUAAGGCUCACCCUAAUUUAGUAUGAACCCAUCUUAACUUGAUUAUAUCUGCAAAGACUCUAUUUCCAAAUGAAGUCAGACUCACAGGUAUUGGGGGUUUGAUAUUGAACAUAUCUUCUGGGAGGAGACACAACUUAAUCAUUAAUAUCCACUUUCUUUUUUCCUUAUUAAAUGUUUAAUUUUUUUGUUUUCAUUAAAACUGUUGUUCGAUUAUGGGUGCUUCACAUAAAAGGUUGGAAACUUAAAAAUUUGUCUCUGACCCCUCCUGGUUGGAAAGGCCUCUGUUGUACAUUUAUGCUAGCCUAGGCCAUACCACUUUCUGUCUUCAGUACAGCCAUCUUAGUUUAUUCAAGUGACACAGAUUUUCCAGAACACAGUAUUCAUGAUCUUUUAAAGCAUUUUUCUUCAAAGACUUUGAUCUGGCAAUAAAUGUUACUAUGUAAUUCUCAUGACAUAAAUUAGGCAUAACUUGGAUCUCCUCUUCUUCUGCUCAUUCAUUUGUCUGAAUCAUCACUAUUAUCUUUUUUAUAUUCCUUUACCGUUCUCCAUAAUGCUUUUCCAAGAAACUGGUUUAUUCCACAAUUUUAUUGCAGAGGCAGCUGCAGGAUAUCAUAAUCUUAUCUUUAUACGAAGGAAGAAUUGCCUAAUCCCUCAAGUAAACUAAAAAUGUUUUAUACAGUCAUUUCUCAUUCAUCCAAUGUUCCAGGCAGUCCCAGUCCAAGACUGCCCCUUCACACACACAACAACUCUUCACAAGACUUCACUGUCCUUCAGACUCUCCUGCAGCACAGACAUUCGAGGUUGCUGAGUCGACAUUGCAGUUAUUUCACUCUUGAUUUUGCUGCUCAAUUUUAAGUUUCCACACUUAUUGCUAAAACAUUCCUUCUAGUGGAUCUGUUUAUGUAUUCAAGCACACCAUCUGUCACAAUUAUUUCAAAUCACAGGUCUGUGACAGACUGUCAAUUUCACACCACAAAGUAUAAUAGUGGAAAACAAAGUAAAAUCAAGAAAGGGAGAACACUAAACUUAUUAAAACCAUAUACAAGCAUACGCAUUCAGGAAACUAAAACAACCUUCAAAGAAGUUGAACAAUUUUGAGCCAAAAGAAAGGGCAUAUGCACACCCUACCCCAGUAUAAGAUAACCAGAAAAGGACUGGGUGAGUUGCCUCCUGAGUAUUAUGACUGCCAUCAAUCACUUAGGCAUUGGAGAUCAGGAGACUCUUCCCAGGCCACACAUUCUGCAGUGACUGUGAGGGCUGAAUGAAUGCUUCCAGGCCAUCAGGAACAAGCAUAGAAACACAAAUCAAUUUUAAAAUACACUCAAAAAUGUCAAAAUAAUCCAACUUUUUUGUCUUGAUCAGAUAUAUCUACUAGCACAUAUUACUUCAUUUUUUCAGCCAAUAUUUAUUAAUAACCUACUGUGUGCUUGACAGUGUUCUAGUGGCAGAGACACAGCAGUGCAUAAUGCCUUGCCCUCUGAAGCAGAUGUUGCAGCAGGAGGAGACAUUCCAGGACAUGACAAUUAAAGUGGAGGAAUGUCAAGCAGAACUGGGGAAUAAGGGAUGUGAAGGGGGUGAGACUUGCUAUUUUAUAUAGGAUGGUCGGAAAAAGGACUUAUCAGGAGUGACAUUUGAGCAGGGAGAUGAAGAACUGAAGGGAGCAAGCCAAGAAAAGAGGCCCUGAAUUUGGAAAAUACAUGGCACGUUCCAACAAGAGCAGAGAGGACAAACGUGAGCAGAGUAAAGUGAGCAAGAAGAGAUAAUAUAUGAUACAAGGUCAGAAAGGUAAUGACAAUCGCAUCCUGUAGGACUUUUUAGGCCAUUGUAAAGAUGAGCUUUUACUCUGAGUAAGACAGAGAGCUAUUAGAGGGGUCUCGGUAGAGGAGUGACUUGAUUCAACUGUCUUUGAGAGGAUCCCUUUGCGUGUAUAGACUGUAAGGUAACAGGAAUAGGCCAAGAGAGAAUAUUUCGGAUGCUAGUGCAAUAAUCAGGUGAGAGAUGAUGAAGACUUUGACCUGGAUAAUAGUAGAAAAAUUGUUGAGAAGGGAUCAAAAUAUGGGGUUUGUUUUGAUGGUAGAGAGGCCAGGGAUGGCUGAAUGAUCAGAUGGGGCAUGAGAGAGAAAGAAAAGAAACAGAGAUGACUUCAGGAAUUUUGGCCUGGGCCACUGGAAGGAUGAAGUCACCAUUUACUGAGAUGGUAAUGACUGGGAGGUUGAGCUGGAAGAACUGAGAAUCAAAUAUCUGGUUUUGAAUCUGUUCUUUUUGAGAUGCAUAUUCAACUUCCAUAUGGAGGUGUCAAGGAGGAUUUAGAUCUAGAAUUUUGGAGCUCAAGGGAAAGGGUUGAGCUGUAGACAUAAAUUCUAGAGAUGCCGGAAUAUAGAUUGUGAUCCUUCUUUAUCAGCACAGAAAUGACUUGACUUUGUCCAAACUAAGCAAUCAUACUGUACAUGUUAGCAACACAUUUUACAGGGCCAAUUUGGCCUUUUGCAAUGUUCUGUGGUUUCUAAGAUAAAUAAACAUAUUAUAUGUUUCCCUCUGGA